AGAAUAUUUGUGAAGCACGGCGUGUAAGAAGUUGUCUGUGUGAGUGACUGUGAAUAGAGGCUGUCAAUGCGUGAAAGAUGGUUAGGAGACUAAGUGCACUUGAGACUGUGACUGGGUGCGAAGGACUGCGGAUUGUUGUGGAAGCCUGUGCCCAACAGGCCUGUGACACCGUGUCUGUGUGUGAGGUGGACUGGAAGAUUAUGGAAAGAAGGAACGCGGACCCACGUGACGGCUGAGACUGCGGCUGCAUGUGGGAAAGGUCUUGUGGGUGUUAGGGAGACUGUAUUGUGUGCGAGAAGGUCGCCUGCGAGGCCGCUGGCCAGGCCUGAGCCUCUGCCACCAUGGCCAUUGUGCAGACUCUGCCAGUGCCACUGGAGCCUGCUCCUGAAGCUGCCACUGCCCCACAAGCUCCAGUCAUGGGUAGUGUGAGCAGCCUUAUCUCAGGCCGGCCCUGUCCCGGGGGGCCAGCUCCUCCCCGCCACCACGGCCCUCCUGGGCCCACCUUCUUCCGCCAGCAGGAUGGCCUGCUACGGGGUGGCUAUGAGGCACAGGAGCCGCUGUGCCCAGCUGUGCCCCCUAGGAAGGCUGUCCCUGUCACCAGCUUCACCUACAUCAAUGAGGACUUCCGGACAGAGUCACCCCCCAGCCCAAGCAGUGAUGUUGAGGAUGCCCGAGAGCAGCGGGCACACAAUGCCCACCUCCGCGGCCCACCACCAAAGCUCAUCCCUGUCUCUGGAAAGCUGGAGAAGAACAUGGAGAAGAUCCUGAUCCGCCCAACAGCCUUCAAGCCAGUGCUGCCCAAACCUCGAGGGGCUCCGUCCCUGCCUAGCUUCAUGGGUCCUCGGGCCACCGGGCUGUCUGGGAGCCAGGGCAGCCUGACGCAGCUGUUUGGGGGCCCUGCCUCCUCCUCCUCCUCUUCCUCCUCCUCUUCAGCUGCUGACAAACCCCUGGCAUUUAGUGGCUGGGCCAGUGGCUGCCCAUCAGGGACGCUAUCCGACUCUGGCCGAAACUCACUGUCCAGCCUGCCCACCUACAGCACCGGAGGUGCCGAGCCAACCACCAGCUCCCCAGGCGGGCACCUGCCUUCCCAUGGCUCUGGGCGAGGGGCACUGCCUGGGCCAGCCCGAGGGGUCCCUACUGGGCCCUCCCACUCAGACAGUGGCCGGUCCUCCUCCAGCAAGAGCACAGGCUCCCUAGGGGGCCGUGUGGCUGGGGGGCUUUUGGGCAGUGGUACUCGGGCCUCCCCUGACAGCAGCUCCUGUGGGGAGCGCUCACCACCACCCCCGCCUCCACCUCCUUCGGAUGAGGCCCUGCUGCACUGUGUCCUGGAAGGAAAGCUCCGAGACCGGGAGGCAGAGCUUCAGCAGCUGCGGGACAGUCUGGACGAGAAUGAGGCUACCAUGUGCCAGGCAUACGAGGAGCGGCAGCGGCACUGGCAGCGAGAGCGUGAGGCCCUGCGAGAGGACUGUGCGGCCCAGGCACAGCGGGCACAGCGGGCCCAACAGCUGCUGCAGCUGCAGGUGUUCCAGCUGCAGCAGGAGAAGCGGCAAUUGCAGGACGACUUCGCACAGCUGCUGCAGGAGCGCGAACAGCUGGAGCGGCGCUGCGCCACCUUGGAGCGGGAGCAGCGGGAGCUCGGGCCGAGGCUUGAGGAGACCAAGUGGGAGGUGUGCCAGAAAUCAGGCGAGAUCUCCCUGCUGAAGCAGCAGCUGAAAGAGUCUCAGGCAGAGCUGGUGCAGAAGGGCAGCGAGCUGGUGGCUCUGCGGGUGGCGCUGCGGGAGGCCCGUGCUACGCUGCGGGUCAGUGAGGGCCGUGCGCGGGGUCUACAGGAGGCCGCCCGAGCUCGGGAGCUGGAGCUGGAAGCCUGUUCCCAGGAGCUGCAGCGACACCGCCAGGAAGCUGAGCAGCUGCGGGAGAAAGCUGGGCAGUUGGAUGCUGAGGCGGCCGGACUCCGGGAGCCCCCUGUGCCACCUGCCACCGCUGACCCAUUCCUCCUGGCAGAGAGUGAUGAGGCCAAAGUGCAGCGGGCAGCAGCCGGGGUUGGGGGCAGCUUGCGGGCCCAGGUGGAGCGAUUGCGGGUGGAGCUGCAGCGGGAGCGGCGGCGGGGUGAGGAGCAGCGGGACAGCUUUGAGGGGGAGCGGCUGGCCUGGCAGGCAGAGAAGGAGCAGGUGAUCCGCUACCAGAAGCAGCUGCAGCACAACUACAUCCAGAUGUACCGGCGCAACCGGCAGCUAGAGCAGGAGCUGCAGCAGCUCAGCCUGGAGCUGGAGGCCCGGGAGCUCGCUGACCUGGGCCUGGCCGAGCAGGCCCCCUGCAUCUGCCUGGAGGAGAUCACUGCUACUGAGAUCUAGGGCCCUCAGCAACCAGCUCUGUAGGGAGCUCUGCCAGAGGGGCAGCAGCUGCAGAUCCACUUAGGCCCCAGGGUCCACGGAUGGCCCCAAAGGCUGAGGGCCCCAAAGCCACUUGUCUCCUAGGAUCCAGGCCUCUGGGCUUCUGCCAAGAACUCAGGGUGGCCCUAUGACUUGGAGGAGCAAGAUCAGACCGCUCAAAGGUCCCCGUGUUCACUGUUACCCAGAGGCUCUUGUUACUACCCACUUCAUUCCCCACCGCUGCCAGUGCCACUGCCAACCCUGUUCACAGGCGCUUCCAGCCCACUCCAGCCAGGGGAGCAGGGAAGAAGAAGGGGCUCCCUCCUCUUCACAUUCCCCCCGACCCCAAAGCCAGAGAAAGCCAGAUGGCACCAGCUGCUCCGGAUGUGCCUGCCCACAUUGGGGGACAGGGCCGGGCCUGGGCUCGGUUCCCAGGUUUGAGCUCUGCAGCCUCUCUCCUGGAGUGAGGGGGCUGAAGUCAGACCAAAGGAAGAACUCAGAAAUGUCUUGUUUAUUUGUGUUUGUGACCAAGCAGCCUCUCCCUUCACCCAGGUUUAUGGCCUCGUUUUCACUUGUAUAUUUUUCACACUGUAAAUUUCUUGUACAAACCCAAAGAAAAAAUUAAAAAAAAUUUUUUUGUUUAAAAA